AUGGGCGGGCGUCCUCGGCUCUAACUGCCGCCACUUUCCACACGCUGGGAGGGCCGUUACCUCAGAGAUACCCGUGGCCGGCAUGUUGGUUGAAAAAGCUUCCCGGAAGGGAGACGAAGAGAAAGGAGAGGAGCAGCUCGUGAUCAUCCCCGGUAGCGAGUACGCGGCGAAGUAGGCGGCGGCGGAGGGAGCGCUGAUGAAGAUGGAUGUGUCAGUGAGGGCCGCGGGCUGCUCCGACGACCUCAGCUCUGGGGAGGCCGACGUAGACCCAAAGCUCCUGGAGCUCACCGCUGACGAGGAGAAGUGCCGCAGCAUCCGCAGGCAGUACCGGCAGCUCAUGUACUGCGUGCGGCAGAACCGGGAGGACAUCGUGAGCUCGGCGAACAACUCCUUAACCGAGGCUCUGGAGGAAGCCAACGUCCUCUUUGAUGGCGUGAGCCGAACCAGAGAAGCAGCCCUCGACGCCCGGUUUCUUGUUAUGGCUUCUGAUUUGGGUAAAGAAAAGGCAAAGCAGUUAAACUCAGAUAUGAACUUCUUUAAUCAGUUAGCAUUUUGUGACUUUCUGUUUCUGUUCGUGGGUCUGAAUUGGAUGGAAGGCGAUCCUGACAAGUUGAGUGAUUGUGAUGAUAGCAUAGCUCUUUCCUUCUGGAAGGCAAUAGAAAAGGAAGCAACAUCCUGGAUGGUAAAAGCUGAGACAUUCCAUUUUGUUUUUGGUUCAUUCAAGCUAGAACGUUCUGCACCAAAGCCCCGACUUGAACACCAGAAAAAAGUUCGCAAGAUGGAAGAAAAUGGCAACAUGCCUACAAAGUUGCAGAAGUUGGACCUGAGUAGUUAUCCAGAAGCGACAGAAAAAAACGUAGAAAGGAUUUUGGGAUUGUUGCAAACCUACUUUCGAAAGUAUCCUGAUACUCCUGUGUCCUAUUUUGAGUUUGUGAUUGAUCCAAACUCUUUUUCUCGUACUGUGGAGAAUAUAUUUUAUGUUUCUUUUAUUGUAAGAGAUGGUUUUGCAAGAAUAAGGCUUGAUGAAGACAGGCUGCCAAUAUUAGAGCCGAUGAAUGUUAACCAAAUGGGUGAGGGAAAUGAUUCCAGUUGCCAUGGCAGGAAACAGGGAGUUAUAUCUUUGACUUUACAGGAGUGGAAAAACAUUGUGGCAGCUUUUGAAAUUUCUGAGGCUAUGAUUACAUACUCCUCAUACUAAAGAUUUCUUAGUAUAGCAUCCUUUUUGUGUUUUUUUUCUGAAGUUAGAUGGAGAGUAAAAUGUAAACUGAAGCACAUAUUGUAUCUCUUGUAAAGUGAAAAAGUAUUUUCAAGAACAUCAGACAUUGUUUUACUGUGCAGCAUAUUUUUCUUAGUAAUUUAUAAGGUCAUGAUCUUCUGUUAUUAAAACAAAUUCACUGGCAUAUUUAUGGGAACGUUUUAUUGAAUGCCCUUUAAGACUAUUAAUAAAAACAAGUUUUGGAUACCAAA